AACGCUCCGCCGGCGCCAAUUUCAAACAGCGGAACAAACUGAAAGCUCCGGUGCCAGACCCCACCCCCGGCCCCGGCCCGGGACCCCCUCCCCUCCCGGGAUCCCCCGGGGUUCCCACCCCGCCCGCACCGCCGGGGACCCGGCCGGUCCGGCGCGAGCCCCCGUCCGGGGCCCUGGCUCGGCCCCCAGGUUGGAGGAGCCCGGAGCCCGCCUUCGGAGCUACGGCCUAACGGCGGCGGCGACUGCAGUCUGGAGGGUCCACACUUGUGAUUCUCAAUGGAGAGUGAAAACGCAGAUUCAUAAUGAAAACUAGCCCCCGUCGGCCACUGAUUCUCAAAAGACGGAGGCUGCCCCUUCCUGUUCAAAAUGCCCCAAGUGAAACAUCAGAGGAGGAACCUAAGAGAUCCCCUGCCCAACAGGAGUCUAAUCAAGCAGAGGCCUCCAAGGAAGUGGCAGAGUCCAACUCUUGCAAGUUUCCAGCUGGGAUCAAGAUUAUUAACCACCCCACCAUGCCCAACACGCAAGUAGUGGCCAUCCCCAACAAUGCUAAUAUUCACAGCAUCAUCACAGCACUGACUGCCAAGGGAAAAGAGAGUGGCAGUAGUGGGCCCAACAAAUUCAUCCUCAUCAGCUGUGGGGGAGCCCCAACUCAGCCUCCAGGACUCCGGCCUCAAACCCAAACCAGCUAUGAUGCCAAAAGGACAGAAGUGACCCUGGAGACCUUGGGACCAAAACCUGCAGCUAGGGAUGUGAAUCUUCCUAGACCACCUGGAGCCCUUUGCGAGCAGAAACGGGAGACCUGUGCAGAUGGUGAGGCAGCAGGCUGCACUAUCAACAAUAGCCUAUCCAACAUCCAGUGGCUUCGAAAGAUGAGUUCUGAUGGACUGGGCUCCCGCAGCAUCAAGCAAGAGAUGGAGGAAAAGGAGAAUUGUCACCUGGAGCAGCGACAGGUUAAGGUUGAGGAGCCUUCGAGACCAUCAGCGUCCUGGCAGAACUCUGUGUCUGAGCGGCCACCCUACUCUUACAUGGCCAUGAUACAAUUCGCCAUCAACAGCACUGAGAGGAAGCGCAUGACUUUGAAAGACAUCUAUACGUGGAUUGAGGACCACUUUCCCUACUUUAAGCACAUUGCCAAGCCAGGCUGGAAGAACUCCAUCCGCCACAACCUUUCCCUGCACGACAUGUUUGUCCGGGAGACGUCUGCCAAUGGCAAGGUCUCCUUCUGGACCAUUCACCCCAGUGCCAACCGCUACUUGACAUUGGACCAGGUGUUUAAGCCACUGGACCCAGGGUCUCCACAAUUGCCCGAGCACUUGGAAUCACAGCAGCAGAAACGACCGAAUCCAGAGCUCCGCCGGAACAUGACCAUCAAAACCGAACUCCCCCUGGGCGCACGGCGGAAGAUGAAGCCACUGCUACCACGGGUCAGCUCAUACCUGGUACCUAUCCAGUUCCCGGUGAACCAGUCACUGGUGUUGCAGCCCUCGGUGAAGGUGCCAUUGCCCCUGGCGGCUUCCCUCAUGAGCUCAGAGCUUGCCCGCCAUAGCAAGCGAGUCCGCAUUGCCCCCAAGGUUUUUGGGGAACAGGUGGUGUUUGGUUACAUGAGUAAGUUCUUUAGUGGCGAUCUGCGAGAUUUUGGUACACCCAUCACCAGCUUGUUUAAUUUUAUCUUUCUUUGUUUAUCAGUGCUGCUAGCUGAGGAGGGGAUAGCUCCUCUUUCUUCUGCAGGACCAGGGAAAGAGGAGAAACUCCUGUUUGGAGAAGGGUUUUCUCCUUUGCUUCCAGUUCAGACUAUCAAGGAGGAAGAAAUCCAGCCUGGGGAGGAAAUGCCACACUUAGCGAGACCCAUCAAAGUGGAGAGCCCUCCCUUGGAAGAGUGGCCCUCCCCGGCCCCAUCUUUCAAAGAGGAAUCAUCUCACUCCUGGGAGGAUUCGUCCCAAUCUCCCACCCCAAGACCCAAGAAGUCCUACAGUGGGCUUAGGUCCCCAACCCGGUGUGUCUCGGAAAUGCUUGUGAUUCAACACAGGGAGAGGAGGGAGAGGAGCCGGUCUCGGAGAAAACAGCAUCUACUGCCUCCCUGUGUGGAUGAGCCGGAGCUGCUCUUCUCAGAGGGGCCCAGUACUUCCCGCUGGGCCGCAGAGCUCCCGUUCCCAGCAGACUCCUCUGACCCUGCCUCCCAGCUCAGCUACUCCCAGGAAGUGGGAGGACCUUUUAAGACACCCAUUAAGGAAACGCUGCCCAUCUCCUCCACCCCGAGCAAAUCUGUCCUCCCCAGAACCCCUGAAUCCUGGAGGCUCACGCCCCCAGCCAAAGUAGGGGGACUGGAUUUCAGCCCAGUACAAACCUCCCAGGGUGCCUCUGACCCCUUGCCUGACCCCCUGGGGCUGAUGGAUCUCAGCACCACUCCCUUGCAAAGUGCUCCCCCCCUUGAAUCACCGCAAAGGCUCCUCAGUUCAGAACCCUUAGACCUCAUCUCCGUCCCCUUUGGCAACUCUUCUCCCUCAGAUAUAGACGUCCCCAAGCCAGGCUCCCCGGAGCCACAGGUUUCUGGCCUUGCAGCCAAUCGUUCUCUGACAGAAGGCCUGGUCCUGGACACAAUGAAUGACAGCCUCAGCAAGAUCCUGCUGGACAUCAGCUUUCCUGGCCUGGACGAGGACCCACUGGGCCCUGACAACAUCAACUGGUCCCAGUUUAUUCCUGAGCUACAGUAGAGCCCUGCCCUUGCCCCUGUGCUCAAGCUGUCCACCAUCCCGGGCACUCCAAGGCUCAGUGCACCCCAAGCCUCUGAGUGAGGACAGCAGGCAGGGACUGUUCUGCUCCUCAUAGCUCCCUGCUGCCUGAUUAUGCAAAAGUAGCAGUCACACCCUAGCCACUGCUGGGACCUUGUGUUCCCCAAGAGUAUCUGAUUCCUCUGCUGUCCCUGCCAGGAGCUGAAGGGUGGGAACAACAAAGGCAAUGGUGAAAAGAGAUUAGGAACCCCCCAGCCUGUUUCCAUUCUCUGCCCAGCAGUCUCUUACCUUCCCUGAUCUUUGCAGGGUGGUCCGUGUAAAUAGUAUAAAUUCUCCAAAUUAUCCUCUAAUUAUAAAUGUAAGCUUAUUUCCUUAGAUCAUUAUCCAGAGACUGCCAGAAGGUGGGUAGGAUGACCUGGGGUUUCAAUUGACUUCUGUUCCUUGCUUUUAGUUUUGAUAGAAGGGAAGACCUGCAGUGCACGGUUUCUUCCAGGCUGAGGUACCUGGAUCUUGGGUUCUUCACUGCAGGGACCCAGACAAGUGGAUCUGCUUGCCAGAGUCCUUUUUGCCCCUCCCUGCCACCUCCCCGUGUUUCCAAGUCAGCUUUCCUGCAAGAAGAAAUCCUGGUUAAAAAAGUCUUUUGUAUUGGGUCAGGAGUUGAAUUUGGGGUGGGAGGAUGGAUGCAACUGAAGCAGAGUGUGGGUGCCCAGAUGUGCGCUAUUAGAUGUUUCUCUGAUAAUGUCCCCAAUCAUACCAGGGAGACUGGCAUUGACGAGAACUCAGGUGGAGGCUUGAGAAGGCCGAAAGGGCCCCUGACCUGCCUGGCUUCCUUAGCUUGCCCCUCAGCUUUGCAAAGAGCCACCCUAGGCCCCAGCUGACCGCAUGGGUGUGAGCCAGCUUGAGAACACUAACUACUCAAUAAAAGCGAAGGUGGACAUGC